UCCGGUCCCGUCCGGAGCGCUCCGGAGGUUGUGGCUGCACAGGCCCUUGCGCCAGGUCGGCCGUGGAGGGCGGCGGAGCCUGCCGGGCGGGGAGAGGCGCGGCGGCGAACGGGGCGGCCGCGGUCCGGGCCGGGGACGCGAGCGGCGGGCGAAAGCGUAGCCUUUCCGCAGCUGAGCGUGAAGGGAUGGAAGCUCUUUAACUUUUAUGAAGUUAUUGCUACUCUGACCUACGACACUCUCCGGUUUGCUGAGUUUGAAGAUUUUCCUGAGACCUCAGAGCCCGUUUGGAUACUGGGUAGAAAAUACAGCAUUUUCACAGAAAAGGACGAGAUCUUGUCUGAUGUGGCAUCUAGACUUUGGUUUACAUACAGGAAAAACUUUCCAGCCAUUGGGGGGACAGGCCCCACCUCGGACACAGGCUGGGGCUGCAUGCUGCGGUGUGGACAGAUGAUCUUUGCCCAAGCCCUGGUGUGCCGGCACCUAGGCCGAGAUUGGAGGUGGACACAAAGGAAGAGGCAGCCAGACAGCUACUUCAGCGUCCUCAACGCAUUCAUCGACAGGAAGGACAGUUACUACUCCAUUCACCAGAUAGCGCAAAUGGGAGUUGGCGAAGGCAAGUCCAUAGGCCAGUGGUACGGGCCCAACACUGUCGCCCAGGUCCUGAAGAAGCUUGCUGUCUUCGAUACGUGGAGCUCCUUGGCGGUCCACAUUGCAAUGGACAACACUGUUGUGAUGGAGGAAAUCAGAAGGUUGUGCAGGACCAGCGUUCCCUGUGCAGGCGCCACUGCGUUUCCUGCAGAUUCCGACCGGCACUGCAACGGAUUCCCUGCCGGAGCUGAGGUCACCAACAGGCCGUCGCCAUGGAGACCCCUGGUACUUCUCAUUCCCCUGCGCCUGGGGCUCACGGACAUCAACGAGGCCUACGUGGAGACGCUGAAGCACUGCUUCAUGAUGCCCCAGUCCCUGGGCGUCAUCGGAGGGAAGCCCAACAGCGCCCACUACUUCAUCGGCUACGUUGGUGAGGAGCUCAUCUACCUGGACCCCCACACCACGCAGCCAGCCGUGGAGCCCACUGAUGGCUGCUUCAUCCCGGACGAGAGCUUCCACUGCCAGCACCCGCCGUGCCGCAUGAGCAUCGCGGAGCUUGACCCGUCCAUCGCUGUGGGGUUUUUCUGUAAGACUGAAGAUGACUUCAAUGAUUGGUGCCAGCAAGUCAAAAAGCUGUCUCUGCUUGGAGGUGCCCUGCCCAUGUUUGAGCUGGUGGAGCUGCAGCCUUCACAUCUGGCCUGCCCCGACGUCCUGAACCUGUCCCUAGGUGAGAGCUGCCAAGUCCAGGUGGGGUCCCUCGGAGGUACGAUCUGUGCCCUUGCUUCCCCAGUCCUGGCCCCCUUGGUUUUGACCAUUAAGGUGUGUGUGAGCCUGAGCCGUGAGCACUUGGCAGUGGUUCGCCUGUGAGACCAGGUAUGGAGUGGAGCGUCCCCUCCUCCAAGCUUGCGCCCAGCAGCCCAGGACCCACCUCGUCUUCCCCACCAGCGCUGCCUGCCCGGGCGCUGUGGAGCUGGGCGUGCUACCAUGGAGUCCUCAGGGGUCUGGAGCAGACAGAACAUGCAGGCUCUGUGGUGACGCAGUCCUGGGUGGGGGACUGGUUCACUUGGGCACCACUGGCCAUGGGUGGCGUAGACCCCUCGGACCAUGGCCAGCGUGCCGCAGGAGCCGGCCUGGGCUCGUGCAGUGAAGUGAGUGGCCGUGAGCGCGUCCUCCUCAUCUCUGUCUCCCUGUGGGAAACUCUACAAACAAGGCAAUGGCAAUGGAACCACUCCUGAUGACCACGAGGGUCAGACGCGGGACAGAGGCCCCUCAGGCCUGAGAUUGUGCCGGCCGCCCCCUGCCCUCCUCACCCUGCCCUGCUCCUCUUCUCUGCUCCCUCCCCCCAUAUUCGCAGGUCUGCACAACCCCCGGACCUGUUCACACCCGCAUGGGGACAGCUGUCUGUGGGCUGCAGAGCAGGCACUGCUCAGUCUGCCCCACGCCAAGGGCCCUUGACUCACACCCAGGUGGCCCACCCAAGAUGCCUGAUGCGCUAUGUCCUGUUCCUUCUAGAUUCUUCUGAUGUAGAGCGACUGGAAAGAUUCUUCGACUCAGAAGAUGAAGACUUUGAAAUCCUGUCCCUUUGAAAAUCCUGGGGUCGGGGGUGGCACCUGUGAGAGCCUGGGGCUCCUGGUGCCGCUGCGUUUCAUCCAUCCCGCCCGCUCGCCUGCCGAGGGCUGCGCCCCGUGCUGCCUCCCCCCAGAGGGCCACCCGCUGUGCUCGUGGACUGAGGCUGCGCUGCCCGGGAGGCCUUACUGCUUGGUGUCAGACUGCCCAGCUCAGAGUGCCCGUCAGGGCCUGUGCAUCCGCACGCGGAGCCGUCUGUUAGGAGCUUCCAGAGUGUUCUCUCGACACUGCCAGCCCCGUGUUAGCACCUGGGCCUCAGUCCCACUUGCUCCCAGGCGCCGGUUCUGUGGUUGGUUUGGAAUUAAAGUCCUGUUUGAAGUUGUCAGACACAGACAUGAAUUUCUGGGCGCUCCCUGAGUCAGAGUCUCAGAAGACCUGUGCAGGCUGGCGUGAGAGGAGCGGCAGCCACACUGCGGCCCCACGCCCAAGGACUGGGCUGCUCUCGAGGGGGGCGCGCCCACCGCUGUGUCCUCUCUGCCCAGCCUGGCUUACCAAGGGCUACCUCAGUGGGAGAUGAGGUUGGAGGAACGAAGGCGAGGUUCCUCCUUGCUUUGGGGAGAAAAGUAUUCAGGAAGUGGGUGUGUGGGAAACCUGAAGAUGGCGUGCACAGGACACAGCGUGGGCGGCCUGGGCAGAAGGGCGGCUGGCUGUCCUGGAGCUGCUGCUGGAGCCUGCCCUCAGAGUGUCCCUUUCCAGUGCUGUGGCAUUCUGUGGCAGCUUCCCCAGGUGUGGUGACGGGGGGGGGGCGGGGCCUCCACCUGUGACAGCCAGGCUUGAGGGUGGACGGCGUGCCUCUCCCAGGAGCCUUCCCCAUGUCCUUGCCUUGCUGAGAAUUGCCCUCCCAUGCCGCUGAGGUGUUAGGUGGUUUAGGGCCAAAAGGGGAAAACCACUUGAGUCUUGUGGUGUGUGGUGGGCAGACACCACAGGGUGGCAUCACCUGGUGGCAUUUCCAGAACCUCAGCCCCGAUUCCAGCACCCACCACCGCCUGACCCUGUGUAACCUGCUGUCCCGGGUCCCAGAGUGCACUCUGCCCCGCUGCUCUGCUGCCUGUCCUGGGAAAGUAUCUUUGCCCCACUAGGAAAUGUAAACAGGAGGGCUUGGGGAGCGUGGGCACUUUUCUCAUGAGCAGCUACUGCGGCGUUGGCAGGACUCGCUGCUGCUGCUGCUGCUUGUGUAGGUCGGGGAGCCAGAGAUCCCCGAGGACGCGCGCCGGACAGUCGGCACUGACCGGCCCACCUGGUAGCAGAGGACACCCCCAGCCCCCCAAGCAUUGAAGACAUAGUGUAUUUCCUCGUAUCCUUUCUCCCUUGGGUGUAGUUGGGGUGGGGAAGCAGGGAAGGCUGGUGCGAUCUCCAUUCCUUGGGCUCCACGUCCGAGUUCAUGGUGCGCCGCUGUGCUGGGAGCUGCAGUGGUAAUGUGUGGGACACCUUGACCAAAGGGGAGCUUUGUCUCGUGUGUUUUGAAAAAGGCUUAAUGAAGAGAAUGUUGUUCAUUCUUAGUAGUAUAGUUUGCAAUUCUUAAUGGCAAAUAAUAAGUUUCAGUAGAAAACAAA